AUUUCGGGUCUGCGAGGUGGGGUAGGCGGGCAAGGCGGGCGCCGAGGUUUGCAAAGGCUCGCAGCGGCCAGAAACCCGGCUCCGAGCGGCGGCGGCCCGGCUUCCGCUGCCCGUGAGCUAAGGACGGUCCGCUCCCUCUAGCCAGCUCCGAAUCCUGAUCCAGGCGGGGGCCAGGGGCCCCUCGCCUCCCCUCUGAGGACCGAAGAUGAGCUUCCUCUUCAGCAGCCGCUCUUCUAAAACAUUCAAACCAAAGAAGAAUAUCCCUGAAGGAUCUCAUCAGUAUGAACUCUUAAAACAUGCAGAAGCAACUCUAGGAAGUGGGAAUCUGAGACAAGCUGUUAUGUUGCCUGAGGGAGAGGAUCUCAAUGAAUGGAUUGCUGUGAACACUGUGGAUUUCUUUAACCAGAUCAACAUGUUAUAUGGAACUAUUACAGAAUUCUGCACUGAAGCAAGCUGUCCAGUCAUGUCUGCAGGUCCGAGAUAUGAAUAUCACUGGGCAGAUGGUACUAAUAUUAAAAAGCCAAUCAAAUGUUCUGCACCAAAAUACAUUGACUAUUUGAUGACUUGGGUUCAAGAUCAGCUUGAUGAUGAAACUCUUUUUCCUUCUAAGAUUGGUGUCCCAUUUCCCAAAAACUUUAUGUCUGUGGCAAAGACUAUUCUAAAGCGUCUGUUCAGGGUUUAUGCCCAUAUUUAUCACCAGCACUUUGAUUCUGUGAUGCAGCUGCAAGAGGAGGCCCACCUCAACACCUCCUUUAAGCACUUUAUUUUCUUUGUUCAGGAGUUUAAUCUGAUUGAUAGGCGUGAGCUGGCACCUCUUCAAGAAUUAAUAGAGAAACUUGGAUCAAAAGACAGAUAAAUGUUUCUUCUAGAACACAGUUACCCCCUUGCUUCAUCUAUUGCUAGAACUAUCUCAUUGCUAUCUGUUAUAGACUAGUGAUACAAACUUUAAGAAAACAGGAUAAAAAGAUACCCAUUGCCUGUGUCUACUGAUAAAAUUAUCCCAAAGGUAGGUUGGUGUGAUAGUUUCCGAGUAAGACCUUAAGGACACAGCCAAAUCUUAAGUACUGUGUGACCACUCUUGUUGUUAUCACAUAGUCAUACUUGGUUGUAAUAUGUGAUGGUUAACCUGUAGCUUAUAAAUUUACUUAUUAUUCUUUUACUCAUUUACUCAGUCAUUUCUUUACAAGAAAAUGAUUGAAUCUGUUUUAGGUGACAGCACAAUGGACAUUAAGAAUUUCCAUCAAUAAUUUAUGAAUAAGUUUCCAGAACAAAUUUCCUAAUAACACAAUCAGAUUGGUUUUAUUCUUUUAUUUUACGAAUAAAAAAUGUAUUUUUCAGUAUCCUUGAGAUUUAGAACAUCUGUGUCACUUCAGAUAACAUUUUAGUUUCAAGUUUGUAUGGUAGUGUUUUUAUAGAUAAGAUACGUCUAUUUUUUCAAAAUUCAUGAUUGCAGUUUAAAUCAUCAUAUGACGUGUGGGUGGGAGCAACCAAAGUUAUUUUUACAGGGACUUUAUUUUUUGAUCUUUAUUUGAGAUUGUUUUCAUAUCUAUCUAAAUUAUUAGGAGUGUGUGUAUCAGAAGUAAUUUUUUAAUGUCUUCUAAGGAUGGUCUUCCAGGCUUUUAAACUGAAAAGCUUAAUUCAGAUAGUAGCUUUUGGCUGAGAAAAGGAAUCCAAAAUAUUAAUAAAUUUAGAUCUCAAAACCACUAUUUUUAUUAUUUCAUUAUUUUUCAGAGGCCUUAAAAUUCUGGAUAAGAGAAUGGAGGAAAAUACUCAGAGUACUUGAUUAUUUUAUUUCCUUUUAUUAAAAAAUUACUUCUAUGUUUUUAUUGUCUCUUGAGCCUUAGUUAAGAGUAGUGUAGAAAUGCAUGAACUUCAUCCUAAUAAGGAUAAAACUUAAGGAAAACCACAAUAAACCAUGAAGGUGUACACAUCUUAUAACACAGAUAAAGUUUUGGUGUGCUACCUAUUCUUGAGAGAGUGAGUGAGUGUAUGUGUUUAAAGGAAACAAAAUGGGAGAAAUAAGUUUUAAAAAAAUCCUCAUUUUGUUAAUAUUCAAAAGAUGGACUGAGCUUCCACUUGGGUUUUAUCUUGUUUUAAUUGUUUUUGUAUCAAAACUUGAAAUUCCUCUAUUUCUAUUGGGAUAUAAAAGCCUUCCCCUUCAGUGAAGAAAACAUUUAUUUUUUAUUUGAUUCCUAGGAUUUAGUAAACUCUAGCUGUCUAUUUAAAAUGUACUGAGGCACAACAAGUAUUAUACUGGAAGACUUGCCAAACUGGCAAAGCUUUAAGUUCAUCAGCAUUCUAUGUGGUUCAGAGCUGUGAUUUUUGCAAAGUAUUUUACCAACCUCCUCGAUGGCUUUGAUAAAGGUUAGAUUUGAUGUUUUUUUUUAGAUUUAUUUUUCUUACUCCACUAAACUAUAAAGAAAAUAAUUACUUAGAAACUCCAUUUUAAAUAAUCAUUUCCUAGAAAUUCUUAAAUAUAUACAGAAUUUUAAAGAAAACAUUUCAUCUGAUUUAGUUAGCAUCCACAUAUCAUUGAGGAAUUAAAGUGUGGGACAGUCAUUAUUAAAAAAAAGAGAGAAAAGCCCUCUAUUAGACAUUCCACAAUCCAUGUUUUAAGCUUAUCCAAAGGUCCAAAUGUCAGCCAUUCUGUAUGUUCAUGUUGAUCAUUUGCGAACAAGAAAGCAGGUUUCUAGGUAUCACUUAGGAUGUGAACUGCCUCUCAACUUUAAACCCUGUUAGCUUUACUUUUUUAAGUCCACAAGUGAUGAAACUAGUUUCUCAGCUAGGCUUGUACUUUCCUCAUUAUUUCUAGUAUUUCAAAUAUUCUCAAACAAAAGAGUUACCACUUUUCUCCAUUUAUUUUCAGUUAUGGAAAUGUUCCCUCUCUUCACCACUAAGCUCCAAAGCAAAUGAAAGACGAUCACAUGUCAGGACAGUAGUAAAGGCAGCUUAUAAAUGGGACAUAAAUCAGAGAUGUGUUGGUAUUUUGAGACUCAAGACUGUCCUUUUUUAAAAUAAAAAUAAAAACAUUACCAGGUUCCCAAGCCAAUCUGGCUUAACCAACAGUGCACUGAAAUAUUAGUGUUUACCUCCAAGGCUAGGGAGCCAAGGGGAGGAGGAGAAUUGGAGGAAGGGGAGAUAAUGGGAAGAGGAUGGCGCCUUCCUGAGUUGGCUAGAGGGCCAACCUUUGAUAACAGUUUGACGAAAUCAAUCUUUUUUUUUUUUUUUUUUGAGACAGAGUCUCACUCUGUCACCCAGGCUGGAGUACAGUGGUGGGAUCUCGGCUCACUGCAAGCUCUGCCUCCCAGGUUCAUGCCAUUCUCCUGCCCCAGCCUCUCCUGAGUAGCUGGAACUACAGGUGCCCGCCACCACGCCCAGCUAAUUUUUUCUAUUUUUAGUCAUGCCUGGCUAAUUUUUUGUAUUUUUAGUAGAGAUGGGGUUUCACCGUGUUAGCCAGGAUGGUCUCCAUCUCCUUACCUCGCAAUCCGCCCGCCUCAGCCUCCCAAAGUGUUGGGAUUACAGGCAUGAGCCACCGUGCCCGGCCUAUAGAAAUCAAUCUUUUUGACUCUUCUCACUUUUAUCUCCCCAUGCCCAAGGUUUGCCUGUUCCAUAACACUCACUCCCUUCCCCCUUGCUAAUCAGAAGCCAUCUCCUCUCAGUGUCUGAUCUCUGCUCUUCAUACAUGAUUACAGUCAUGGGGUAGAGAGUGCUUGCUAAAUUAUGCAGUUAAUCCUAUGGUGCUUUAAUUUUCAGGCCUUCAAAAAACACUUGUACAGUGAUGUGCAGAUUUUUAAACAGUUGAACUUCCUUGUACUACAGUUUUUGUAUUGACAGCCAAAUUUGUCUUUCAUUCUUCAGAUUGUGAAUAAAGUGAUUUUUACAGGGCUUCCAGCAAAGUUUUUCCUUUCAUCUAAGGCUUGUAGAACCCUAGCUUAUAUAGCUGCUUACAUGAGAAAUGCAAAAUCUGUAUUCACCAUGACUUUAGUAACAAAGGUAAAGUUUUUUAGUAGUGCCAAGGCAAGAGGAACAAUCUUGGUGGUAGUACUAAGUUUUGUCAAUAUUGUGGUUUCCUGAUUGUAUUGUUGGCUUUCUCUCUGAGCAUUGAGGUAUACUAGAAGUAGAGCUUCUCAAACAUAAUAUCAUUACCUCAUAAGCAUUAACAAAUCAGGCCCAAAGAGCGUAAGUCCUAGAAAUUUGUUUUAAAGCAGCCCUAGUCAUGGUGCUGGUGCUACCGCCUUGUUUUAGGAGCCUGCCUCCUGUCAGUAUGAAACCCUCACCUGAAAAAUGCCAGCCUGGACACCAAACACUGAGCCCCUUCAACAGGCACAUUAUUUCCCCCUGAGAUCCAUAAGGGAAUUUAGUUUCUACUAUUGUAGAGUUCUGAAAAGAGGUAAAAUAGUAGUCCUUUGGUCAUCCUAUUUUUGCUUUCAAUUUUGAUAUUUCAGACUGUAAAAGGCCUUGGGGGAUGAUAGUACAUGUGGUAGCAGUAAUUUUUUUGAAGCAACUGCACUGACAUUCAUUUGAGUUUUCUCUCAUUAUCAGAUUCUGUUCCAAACAAGUAUUCUGUAGAUCCAAAUGGAUUACCAGUGUGCUACAGACUUCUUAUUAUAGAACAGCAUUCUAUUCUACAUCAAAAAUAGUUUGUGUAAGUUAGUUUUGGUUACCAUCUAAAAUAUUUUUAAAUGUUCUUUACAUAAAAAUUUAUGUUGUGUUUUAAAAUCCUUAGGGGCUUUAUCUAUUUUUCUAAGUCAGUUAACUGUACUUCUAAAAAAAGUAUUUUGUAUCUACUUUUGUAACUUCGUCAGAAUAAAAUAUAUUGAAAGCAAGAAAUGACUGAUUAAAGUAUGUAUAUCAACACACAUUUCUAUUUAAAUAUAGAAACUUGAGAGUUUUGCA